GGGCAGGUGGGCUAGCCAUGAACAGAAGAGGAAGCUGGAGUGCUUUGGGGGUUCAUGCAUGUAGGCUGGGAUUUGGGGCUCACACCUCAACCUGCAUGCCCAGUUCCAUGCCCCUCCCCUCUUGUGAAAGCACCUGUCUACUUGGGCUGAGGAUGUGGGGGCACAGGUGGCAGGUGAGGCUGCCCUCAGGAGGGGCCCAGGCCCAGCUUGUACCCCACCUCCACCAGUACCUGAAGAAGUGGGGCUCUCACCCUACCUGCCUCUGCCAUUGGAAUGGCCUGGUUUGCACAGAUGGGAAACCCGUUUGCGGGGUGGGUGUCUGGGUGGGCACGUGGGGCGAGGACCUGCCUGCGGGACCCUGCCCUGGAACUGACAGUGCAAGCUCGGCGUCCUGCCCAUCUGGGCAGAAGGCUGGUUUCUCCCAUCAACGAAGCCCUCCCAGGACCUUCCUGCAAGCCCUCGUCCCACACGCAGCUCUGCCGUCCCUUGGUGUCCCUCCCGGCCUCAGGUCCUCCAUGCUGGGUACCUCUGGGCACCUCGUUUGGCUGAGCCAGGGGUUCAGCCUGGCAGGGCGCCCUGGCAGCAGUCCUUGGCCUGUGGAUGCUGUCCUGGCCCGUGGAUGGUGUCCCGGCCUCCACGUACCCCUCUCAGCCCCUCCUCUUGGACUCCAGCCAUGGGCCUGCGCGCGAGCCGGAACUGCUCCAGGACAGAGAACGCCGUGUGUGGCUGCAGCCCAGGCCACUUCUGCAUCGUCCAGGACGGGGACCACUGCGCCGCGUGCCGCGCUUACGCCACCUCCAGCCCGGGCCAGAGGGUGCAGAAGGGAGGCACCGAGAGUCAGGACACCCUGUGUCAGAACUGCCCCCCGGGGACCUUCUCUCCCAAUGGGACCCUGGAGGAAUGUCAGCACCAGACCAACCGAGCUUGGAAAAGUCAGACAGACCUCUGAGGUCUCAUCCUGGAGCUGCCACCAGCCCAGCCUCCCUGGGACCUGUCUUCACUGCCUGGGGCCCUGGGAGCCAGGGAGGCUCCCUGAGGCUGAGUGAACACUGGGCGCUGCACCUGCCUCUCCCACGUCCUCGGCCCCACUCCCGCAGGUGCAGCUGGCUGGUGACGAAGGCCGGAGCUGGGACCAGCAGCUCCCACUGGGUAUGGUGGUUUCUCUCAGGGAGCCUCGUCAUCGUCAUUGUUUGCUCCACAGUUGGCCUAAUCAUAUGUGUGAAAAGAAGAAAGCCAAGGGGUGAUGUAGUCAAGGUGAUCGUCUCCGUCCAGCGGAAAAGACAGGAGGCAGAAGGUGAGGCCACAGUCAUUGAGGCCCUGCAGGCCCCUCCGGACGUCACCACGGUGGCCGUGGAGGAGACAAUACCCUCAUUCACGGGGAGGAGCCCAAACCACUGACCCACAGACUCUGCACCCCGACGCCAGAGAUACCUGGAGCGACGGCUGCUGAAAGAGGCUGUCCACCUGGCGGAACCACCGGAGCCCGGAGGCUUGGGGGCUCCGCCCUGGGCUGGCUUCCGUCUCCUCCAGUGGAGGGAGAGGUGGGGCCCCUGCUGGGGUAGAGCUGGGGACGCCACGUGCCAUUCCCAUGGGCCAGUGAGGGCCUGGGGCCUCUGUUCUGCUGUGGCCUGAGCUCCCCAGAGUCCUGAGGAGGAGCGCCAGUUGCCCCUCGCUCACAGACCACACACCCAGCCCUCCUGGGCCAGCCCAGAGGGCCCUUCAGACCCCAGCUGUCUGCGCGUCUGACUCUUGUGGCCUCAGCAGGACAGGCCCCGGGCACUGCCUCACAGCCAAGGCUGGACUGGGUUGGCUGCAGUGUGGUGUUUAGUGGAUACCACAUCGGAAGUGAUUUUCUAAAUUGGAUUUGAAUUCGGCUCCUGUUUUCUAUUUGUCAUGAAACAGUGUAUUUGGGGAGAUGCUGUGGGAGGAUGUAAAUAUCUUGUUUCUCCUCAAA